AUCCGGUGCUUGCGUGUGGUGGUGAGCGCAGCGCCGAGGAUGAGGAGGUGCAACAGCGGCUCCGGGCCGCCGCCGUCGCUGCUGCUGCUGCUGCUGUGGCUGCUCGCGGUUCCCGGCGCUAACGCGGCCCCGCGGUCGGCGCUCUAUUCGCCUUCCGACCCGCUGACGCUGCUGCAGGCGGACACGGUGCGCGGCGCGGUGCUGGGCUCCCGCAGCGCCUGGGCCGUGGAGUUCUUCGCCUCCUGGUGCGGCCACUGCAUCGCCUUCGCCCCGACGUGGAAGGCGCUGGCCGAAGACGUCAAAGCCUGGAGGCCGGCCCUGUAUCUCGCCGCCCUGGACUGUGCUGAGGAGACCAACAGUGCAGUCUGCAGAGACUUCAACAUCCCUGGCUUCCCGACUGUGAGGUUCUUCAAGGCCUUUACCAAGAACGGCUCGGGAGCAGUAUUUCCAGUGGCUGGUGCUGACGUGCAGACACUGCGGGAGAGGCUCAUUGACGCCCUGGAGUCCCAUCAUGACACGUGGCCCCCAGCCUGUCCCCCACUGGAGCCUGCCAAGCUGGAGGAGAUUGAUGGAUUCUUUGCGAGAAAUAACGAAGAGUACCUGGCUCUGAUCUUUGAAAAGGGAGGCUCCUACCUGGGUAGAGAGGUGGCUCUGGACCUGUCCCAGCACAAAGGCGUGGCGGUGCGCAGGGUGCUGAACACAGAGGCCAAUGUGGUGAGAAAGUUUGGUGUCACCGACUUCCCCUCUUGCUACCUGCUGUUCCGGAAUGGCUCUGUCUCCCGAGUCCCCGUGCUCAUGGAAUCCAGGUCCUUCUAUACCGCUUACCUGCAGAGACUCUCUGGGCUCACCAGGGAGGCUGCCCAGACCACAGUUGCACCAACCACUGCUAACAAGAUAGCUCCCACUGUUUGGAAAUUGGCAGAUCGCUCCAAGAUCUACAUGGCUGACCUGGAAUCUGCACUGCACUACAUCCUGCGGAUAGAAGUGGGCAGGUUCCCGGUCCUGGAAGGGCAGCGCCUGGUGGCCCUGAAAAAGUUUGUGGCAGUGCUGGCCAAGUAUUUCCCUGGCCGGCCCUUAGUCCAGAACUUCCUGCACUCCGUGAAUGAAUGGCUCAAGAGGCAGAAGAGAAAUAAAAUUCCCUACAGUUUCUUUAAAACUGCCCUGGACGACAGGAAAGAGGGUGCCGUUCUUGCCAAGAAGGUGAACUGGAUUGGCUGCCAGGGGAGUGAGCCGCAUUUCCGGGGCUUUCCCUGCUCCCUGUGGGUCCUCUUCCACUUCUUGACUGUGCAGGCAGCUCGGCAAAAUGUAGACCACUCACAGGAAGCAGCCAAGGCCAAGGAGGUCCUCCCAGCCAUCCGAGGCUACGUGCACUACUUCUUCGGCUGCCGAGACUGCGCUAGCCACUUCGAGCAGAUGGCUGCUGCCUCCAUGCACCGGGUGGGGAGUCCCAACGCCGCUGUCCUCUGGCUCUGGUCUAGCCACAACAGGGUCAAUGCUCGCCUUGCAGGUGCCCCCAGCGAGGACCCCCAGUUCCCCAAGGUGCAGUGGCCACCCCGUGAACUUUGUUCUGCCUGCCACAAUGAACGCCUGGAUGUGCCCGUGUGGGACGUGGAAGCCACCCUCAACUUCCUCAAGGCCCACUUCUCCCCAAGCAACAUCAUCCUGGACUUCCCUGCAGCUGGGUCAGCUGCCCGGAGGGAUGUGCAGAAUGUGGCAGCCGCCCCAGAGCUGGCGAUGGGAGCCCUGGAGCUGGAAAGCCGGAAUUCAACUCUGGACCCUGGGAAGCCUGAGAUGAUGAAGUCCCCCACAAACACCACCCCACAUGUGCCGGCUGAGGGACCUGAGGCAAGUCGACCCCCGAAGCUGCACCCUGGCCUCAGAGCUGCACCAGGCCAGGAGCCUCCUGAGCACAUGGCAGAGCUUCAGAGGAAUGAGCAGGAGCAGCCGCUUGGGCAGUGGCACUUGAGCAAGCGAGACACAGGGGCUGCAUUGCUGGCUGAGUCCAGGGCUGAGAAGAACCGCCUCUGGGGCCCUUUGGAGGUCAGGCGCGUGGGCCGCAGCUCCAAGCAGCUGGUCGACAUCCCUGAGGGCCAGCUGGAGGCCCGAGCUGGACGGGGCCGAGGCCAGUGGCUGCAGGUGCUGGGAGGGGGCUUCUCUUACCUGGACAUCAGCCUCUGUGUGGGGCUCUAUUCCCUGUCCUUCAUGGGCCUGCUGGCCAUGUACACCUACUUCCAGGCCAAGAUAAGGGCCCUGAAGGGCCAUGCUGGCCACCCUGCAGCCUGAACCACCUGGGGAGGAGGCGGGAGAGGGAGCUGCCAUCUCUAGGCACCUCAAGCCCCCUGACCCCAUUCCCUCCCCUCCCACCCCUUGCUCCUUGUCUGGCCUAGAAGUGUGGGAAAUUCAGGAAAACGAGUUGCUCCAGUGAAGCUUCUUGGGGUUGCUAGGACAGAGAGCUCCUUUGACACAAAAGACAGGAGCAGGGUCCAGGUUCCCCUGCUGUGCAGGGAGGGCAGCCCCGGGCAGUGGGCAUAGGGCAGCUCAGUCCCUGGCCUCUUAGCACCACAUUCCUGUUUUUCAGCUUAUUUGAAGUCCUGCCUCAUUCUCACUGGAGCCUCAGUCUCUCCUGCUUGGUCUUGGCCCUCAACUGGGGCAAGUGAAGCCAGAGGAGGGUCCCCCAGCUGGGUGGGCUGGAAUGGAACUCCUCACUAGCUGCUGGGGCUCCGCCCACCCUGCUCCCUUCCGGACAAUGAAGAAGCCUUUGCACCCUGGGAGGAAGGACCACCCCGGGCCCUCUAUGCCUGGCCAGCCUCCAGCUCCUCAGACCUCCUGGGUGGGGUUUGGCUUCAGGGUGGGGUUUGGAAGCUUCUGGAAGUCGUGCUGGUCUCCCAGGUGAGGCAAGCCAUGGUUGCUGGGCUGUAGGGUGAGUGGCUUGCUUGGUGGGACCUGACGAGUUGGUGGCAUGGGAAGGAUGUGGGUCUCUAGUGCCUUGCCCUGGCUUAGCUGCAGGAGAAGAUGGCUGCUUUCACUUCCCCCCAUUGAGCUCUGCUCCCUCUGAGCCUGGUCUUUUGUCCUUUUUUAUUUUGGUCUCCAAGAUGAAUGCUCAUCUUUGGAGGGUGCCAGGUAGAAGCUAGGGAGGGGAGUGUCUUCUCUCUCCAGGUUUCACCUUCCAGUGUGCAGAAGUUAGAAGGGUCUGGCGGGGGCAGUGCCUUACACAUGCUUGAUUCCCACGCUACCCCCUGCCUUGGGAGGUGUGUGGAAUAAAUUAUUUUUGUUAAGGCAAGCAUUGGUGUGUUCUUUAACUUGCUACUUGGAGACCUAGUGUCCAGUCUGGACAGAAUGCACAGAGACCAGCCUCACCUGGAAUGCAGCCAGACUCGAUGUCCCUCAGCACACACAGCUCCUGGCCACAGACUGCCCAUAGAACUGUCUGCACCCAAACCCCAUGGCCUUUUCAUGCACGGAGACAGGCCUCUGGAUGUGCAGCCUUGCCACCCCCUGCCCCAAUCCUCCCUGAGAGCUCCUGCCUCAGUGCCCUGGGCUGGUGAGGGAGAAGCCUGUCUGCACCUGCCUAAUUCCAGCUCCUCCAGGAAGCAAGGGCUUGUUUGUCAGAGCUGCAGGGUUGGCCACUCGGUGGGGAGGAGUCAGCCAGGAUUAGAGAGCCUGCCCCUAAUCCGGCCUGCUGGGUUUUACAAGGAUCAGAGCUGCUGAUAAUGAACCUCAUUAAGGGGGAGCAGGAGCCUCAAUCCGAUUUGGUUUUCUCUUUGACAUCUUCACUCUGCUCAGAUGGCCUGGGUGCUAUGUGGAGCAGGUGGGAUGCCAAGGCCACUCCUGCUAUGGGGCAGCUGGGGCUGGGGAGGGAUGGCAGUCUCCCUGCAUGUUUCCCUCGACCUCUUUAGCUGCAGCGCCUUGCUGGGCUCCUGGGUUGGACUCCCUCUCUGUGCCCCUGCUCCAGGCACCCAUUGGCUCCAUCCUCCUGGUUGUGCUCUGCACCCCCUGCUCCCUUGGGCUGGCCCUGGCUGGGGGCCUGAGAGACAGACAGGAACCCACAAUCAGGAGGCAACCCUGGCCUGCAAGAGGAAGACAGAGGCUCCCAGGGCCGGUGCCCUGUGUGCCCACUGCACCAAGGCCGCUGAAUAAGCCUGCCCUUCACCCCCUAAGGGCUCCUUGCCCAAUGCCAAGUGCUGGGGAUUUCUGUCAGCAAGCCCUGUGGCUCCAGUGACGGUAUUUCUAAAGCCAAACUUAGUUACCUAGAAUUAGCGCCAUGUUGGAAACACUGUCGCAGCAGCCCGGGCUGCACAGUGUGUAGCCCAGCCUCCAGGUCCACGGAGUGGUGUGGACCUCCCACCUCACAGCUGCCUCUGGCAGCCAAGCCUCUUUUCGCCCGGCCCCAGCCCCUCUGGUUGAUAAACGGGUGGGCCUCCUCAGCAGCGUGGCUGCCUUUCACCUUGAUUUCCCCAGGGCUCUCGGCAACAUCGAUAAACCAGCCUCGCCCACCAGCUGGGCCCUCCCCCACCCAGUCUGCCAGGCUGGGAGCUGGAGCUUGCUGAGUCUUGAAUGCCCUUCUAGAUGGCUUCUCUAGAGGCUCUCCUGGCAAGAGAGGGUCCCAAGGGGAGCCCUGCAAAGCAAAGGCUCCUUGUCUGGGGCGGGAUAGAGAAUCUCGCCUCUGUCUGGUGUGUUACCUACUGGGGGCACAGGAACAAUUUCCUCAAGGAGACAGUGGCAUGGAGCUUUGAAAGACGAGUAGGUGUUAGCAAGGAAAUAAGGAGGAACGGGGGUUACGGGCAGAGGAGAAAGCACAUGCCAAGUCAGCAAAGAAAAGUAGAAUUCGAAAACUUUUUAAAAAUAUUACUAAGGAUUUUCACAAUGCUGCACUGGGCUAGAAACUGAAGCUAAAACAGAUACGUGGUCCCUGCUGCUAUGGGGCUUCCGUUCUAGAGGCAAGGACAGGUUGUGAUGAGGGUUCUGAAGGAUAGAGACCAAGCAGGGAGGGUGUUGAGGAGGCUUCUGCGAGACCUGAAGGAUGGGAAGCCAGGAAGUGGGAGGGGUGGGGGUCCAGGCUGGAGGGGCCCAAUGUAGGUGUAGAGGGACUACAGCCCUGAGGGGCUGCUCCAUGCGGCAUUCUUGGAGGUCCAAGAGGGGCAGCGCCACCUUGGGCCAGGCUCCUCUCCAGCAGCCUUGGUAUGGGGUGGGGGUGGGAAGACCCCUGAUGCAGCCUGUCCUCUGGGUGUGGGGGUGGAGGAGAGGGCUCCAGGGGACCCAGCCAGCCUUGACCCUGGAGGAAAGUCAGGUGGGCUCAGAGAGAGCCCUCAAAUCUGGGCCCUGGGUCAGGGUGGGGUCAAGUCCAGCCUUGAAGAGAAUGGACUCUGGAAUCUGACGUCUGGGUUUGAAUCCAGCUUCCAACACUCACUGGCUGUGUGACUUUGGGCAAGAUAACUUAUCCCCUUGUCCCCAUGUGUCAUUGGAGAUAAACUACCCACCUACCAGAUUGUUGUACCAUGCUGGGCAAACACUAAGUGCUUAAUAAUGGUAGCCCACUGCUCAUGUCGUGUCGUCUCCUGUCUUGAUACCUGAAAACUCAAGGGGCCCUGUUGUGCUUGGAGGGGGGUGCCGUUCCCACAGGAUAUUCUGUGAAGGGUGUCCCUGGAGCUGGGCCUCCAGGUGGCAAGCCCCAAGCCACCCCGGCAGGUGCCACUGGCCAGAGUUGAACUGAGGUGUUGAGUGGAAAGUGCCUCCCCACCCCCAUCUGCCACAGUAGUAUGGAUUUCCUUCAUGAGAUGGGGCUCCUAAAAUGCCUGAAAUGUGUAUGCUGUUGGAGAAUUGAUGUGUAUGAUUUAUUGAACUUUGCACUCAUUUAAAUCUCAUUUAAUCCUCCAACAACGCAAGAUGAAGAAGCUGAGGCUUAAAGAGAUUAAGAAACAUCCUAUCCCCUUUACUCCCACCAAAAUAAAUACAUUUGCCCUAUUCUCCCAAAUGGUGAGAGGUAGAUCCAGGACUUGACCCCAGAUCCCACCCACUCAACCCUGGAGCUGCAGUCUCUACCCCUUCUAACACAUGUGAUUCUGUUUCAUGUCCUGUUCCAUCGGUAGAGUUACACACUUUCCUGAGACUUUAUAUGGUGGUGCUGCUGGGUGCCAGCCCUUCUUCCCUCCAACAGUGGCAGUAACCACUGUUGUGUGUUGGUGUCAAGGAGUGGGGACACCCUGAAGGAAUCCGCCUUUUCUAGAGCUCUCGCUCCAUUCCCUACAUCGAGGCUGAAGUGCCCUGUCUCGGGUCCUUGUUUUUAGGCCUCGUUUGAAGGAGGGGAAGAAACCAGGUUCGUUGGGCGUGACCUUGGCUCAGCUCGUCUGUGAAAUUGGGGCCGCAGACUUAGUUUGCGGGUCCCUGCUAAAUUCCUCUCCCUCUUCCUGGGAUUCCCAUCCAUGUAUUGCCAGCUACAUGUAGAGUGGAGAGGAGAGGUUUUUCCUGCAGGGCCUUCCAGAGAAAGGAUUCUUGGCCAGAGGAAAUCACAGCCUAUAAGAUCAAUAUCCUGAUAGAAUCCCGGGCCAGGUGUGAGAGGGGAGAGCUCACUCACACCAGCCUGACAGUCUUGGGGCAGAGCGCCCCAUAGGCCUCUGCAGCCCCAUCACUGCCUCAUUCUCCCUCAGGUGCCAAGGAAGCUCCAGGGUGGGCCCAGUAUCCUUCCACAGCAUCCCUCCUCUUCCCCUUCAACACCCCUUUCACCCCUCCCUCCACCACCUCUGAAAGGUGCUCCUUGGGCAGGGCGAUAGGAUUCCCACCCCUAGCUUUAAGAACUAAACCAAACUUCAAGAGGAGCAAUUUAAUCUUCAUACCUGACUCCUUGUCCCUCCUCAGGCAUGCUGUUGUGCAGGACAGAGCCCUGGCUUCUCCUGGAUGUCACACCUGGCCUGUCUCUGACCCUUGCUUUCCCUUUCUCUGCUGCCCUCAAGGGUCAUUCACACCCAAGAGGGUAAGAAGCUGCCCUCUCAUCCCUUCCUCUCCCACCCUGGGCCUCUGCCCUCUGCCUGGCCCCAGCAGCACAGUCUUCUCCAUAGAGAGGGGCUGGGCCAUGGGACCCCAGUUCCUGGGGUCUCGGUGACACAGUUCACUGUUUGCUGCAGAGGAGGCCCCACUCGCAGCCUUGGCCUCUGCCCUGCAGAAGAAUUCCCUGUAACUCACUCACCAAUGGCCGUGGGAGCCAGUGGCCUCGGCGAGGGUCAGUUGGACUGCAUAGCUGCCGGCUGAGUCUCUCUGGCCACCCUCACUGGCCCCAUCACUCCAGGUUGCACUGCUGCCCAGGGGGUUUGUGCCAGGCCUGGGUCACAGUGGAAGAGAGUCUGGAAAUCACAAGGCAGAGGAGGAGACCUUUGCCAAUGUGAGAGAACAAAGUUAAGGGGCAGUCCAUGGGGGCAUUGACCUUACUUAGGUGAGGAGGACUCAGGGAACAUCUACAGACUCUAGGGCUAGGGUGAGAUCCUCCUGAUAGUGCUGGUAGCUCCAGCUGCUGCUUUGGCAAGACUUGGUCGUCUCUAUACUGAGAGAGCAAAAGCUCUUUUCCUGGGGCUGCAUGUUCUUCCAUAGGAAAGUGGGCUUCAGGUGCUGCCUAUUAAACCUCCUGCCUCCCCUGCUGCAGUGCUUUGAUGCCUUUCACCUGUGUCUACCUGCGAACCUCUGCCCACCACGGAAGAGCAGCUCACAUUUGGAAGGGGCUAAAAUUUUUACCUAGUUUGAAUCUGCUCUGCAAUGUCCCCAUCAAGUUCUUAACCAUCCCGGGUUCCAAUGGUUACAGAGUUCUGCCCUGGGGAGGGAGGAAUUGCUUAGCAAAUGAUGUUGAGAAUAGUGAUUAUUUGGGGGAAAAUUCAGGUAAGAUCUCACCUUCAUACCAUAUACCAAAAUACAUCUCAGUAGAUUAGUAAGCUAAUGCAAAAAAAAAAAAAAAAGGGGAAAUAUAAUUGAAUACUUCACUGUUUUUGAAAGCAUGAAAACAAUGGAAAAUGCAACUGAUGUGAGUAAUCCAUCUACUUGACGUCACUUUUAAGAAAUAAGGCCAGGCACGGUGGCUCACGCUUGUAAUCCUAGCACUUUGGGAGGCCGAGGUGGGUGGAUCACGAGGUCAGGAGUUUGAGACCAGCUUGGCCAACAUGGUGAAACCCCCAUCUCUACUAAAAUAUUACACAGGCAUUGUGGCACACAUCUGUAAUCCCAGCUACUCAGGAGGCUGAGGCAGGAGAAUCACUUGAACCUGGGAGGUGGAGGUUGCAGUGAGCUGAGAUCGCGCCAUUGCACUCCAGCCUGGGGGACAGAGCGAGACUCUGUCUCAAAAAAAUAAAAAAAUAAAAAUAAAAAAAUAAAGUAAAGCUACAUAUUUAAAAGCUGGGGAAAUAUAUGCUGUAAAUAUGACAAAGGGCUGUGACUCUUCUGCAACACACCAUUUUAAGAAUGAGCUAGGUCUGCAUUUAUUGACCUGAUAAAAUGUCCCAAGAAGGACACAUUUUUAUAAACAUAAGUUACUAUUGUUAUAUAUAUGCUAACGUUUGUCUAGAAAAAGUCUAGAAAAAUACACACUGAACUGUGAAUAGCAGUUAUAUUUAGAAAGCAACAUUAGGAUGAACUUAAGUCAGGGCUUGGACUAGAGCAAGGCAAGUGAGGUGCCAGGAUGCAAAAGUUAAGGAGACACCUGACCUCAGGGGCCCACAACUGCAGAGCCCCUGACAGUGAGUGUCUCAGUAGCCUCGCCCUAGUCCUGGCUUUCACUUAAAUAUGUUUUCGAAUGUUUGUAAUAAAAUAUUUCUUUUGGAAGGCAAAAAUAGCAAGGAAAAUAAAUAGGAUUAAAGGAUACUAAAGCCCAUUCAAUAAAAUUUGUAGGAGGCCACUGAUUUGGCCUAGGCUCCUAUGAUGUAACCAACAGACCAAACCAAUAUGGAGUCAUUCAUGCUAAAUGAAACUAGUUAGGAGUAUAUUCAUAUAACAAGUGGCUAAGUGUCAGUUACAGCCUCUGAGCUUUAGUCAAUUGUAGGUGGUCAAUAGAUUCAGAUAAGGCAAUCCAGUUAAACUGUAUAUCCCACUUGCUGUUUUCUGUCCCUAAAUUCUCUCUGAGUACACUGCAGCCCUGAAGUUCUUUGAACCUGUUCUGGGUUCUGAGGGCUGUCCAAUUACUGAAUCAUACAUAAAAGCCAAGUAAGAUUUUAAAAUUUGUUAUAAUUUUGGUUUUUAACAACUUCUGUUGUAAAUAAUAAAAGCACUAAAUCCCUACUGAAAAUAAAGGGCCUAAAGACUGAA